ACUCUCCAUCCAGGCCCCAGGCAAGCAGCACCUCCCUGCUCUCCUGCACUCCUGGACACAACCAGCAGCUCCUGCCAUGGACAGGUGGUACCUGGGCGGCAGCCCCAAGGGGGACGUGGACCCGUUCUACUAUGACUAUGAGACCGUUCGCAAUGGGGGCCUGAUCUUCGCUGGACUGGCCUUCAUCGUGGGGCUCCUCAUCCUCCUCAGCAGAAGAUUCCGCUGUGGGGGCAAUAAGAAGCGCAGGCAAAUCAAUGAAGAUGAGCCGUAACAGCAGCCUCGGCGGUGCCACCCACUGCACUGGGGCCAGCUGGGAAGCCAAGCAUGGCCCUGCCUCUGGCGCCUCCCCUUCUUCCCUGGGCUUUAGACCUUUGUCCCCGUCACUGCCAGCGCUUGGGCUGAAGGAAGCUCCAGACUCAAUGUGACCCCCAGGUGGCAUCGCCAACUCCUGCCUCGUGCCACCUCAUGCUUAUAAUAAAGCCGGCGUCAGAGACCGCUGCUUCCCUCACCUGCCUGCCUGUCUCCCUCCUCUGUCACCACCAGCCUCUCCAAGCUCAAGUACAAAUACAGCCGGGUCUCAUUUGUUUUUUCAA